CUGGGCUGGGGGUGGCGGAGAGGUGGGAGGCGGCCCGAGGCGCGGAGUGGCCCUGUCAUCCCCGGGGGCGGCUGGCCGGGGGACCCUGGAGCGCCGGCUUGGACCCCGACCCGGAGACGGGAUAACUUUCUAUUUUUGUUGGGAAGCCUGCGUACUGUUGCUGGUAUUGUUUUGUAAGUGGUGGCGGUGGAGGUGGUUGAUGCGAGAGGAGAGUGCGGGGAGAACCCUGGGCUGUGCUGGGCAUCGCGGCCAAUGUCCAAGGCCAGACCCUAAAAGUUGGACAAAGCCCCUUAACCCUUCUAGGAUAUCAGAGCGACCCCUGGCCCACCCCCUAACCUUAGUCACCCCCACCUCCCGACUCUUUCGUCUUUUUGUUUCGCUUUCUGCAAUCCUUCUCCCUACCACUCCCCCUCCCUCCCGCCCGGAAUUUCUGAAACAAGUCUCAUCCUUCAGGAUUCUAGGGAUUUCAGAGACCGGAAGCUUUAAUUCUAAUUGCAACUACUUUUUCCCCCCACCUCACUCAGUGUACCAAGUGAAGACCACUCACGUGUUGUGUCACUUUAAGCGCGGGUUUGGGAAAUCUCGCUUGCACUUUGGGGCUACAGCAAUAAGAAGCAAUGAAAAGAGGUUAUACGAGUUGAAAUCAAAUUGGAUUUGGAAAUGUUUGCGUUGGAGAGCAGCAGUUUGUUGAGUAUUGAUCGGAUGCACACGAAGCACUGUUUACAUAUUUUAUUAGUCAUUUUCCCUACACUUUGCAAAGCGACUAUAUUAAUAAAUAGAUUGACCCUGGUGAAUAUCUGAAGACGCUGGUUUCUGUGACUAAAUUCAGAAUGUGAUGAUGAAUGUGAAUUCAUUUUAAUGUGUUCCCUUCUCAGCUAAAGCAGGUCAAGACGAGGAAUCCUGUGAAUAUGCAGAGCCCUACACUCGGUGCCAGGCAGUCCAGGCACUCUGGGUGGCAGUCAACUGUACUUUCUUACAAAAGUUUAGGGAUUUGCUGGAACCCACUUGAGAUCCUCACAUACCCAGAUAGCCAAAGGACUUUGUCAAGGAAGGCAUAAGGAGGUGUCCCCAGGGACUGCCUUCUGGCUCAGCAGAGUUCUUUAGCCAAGGGCAGGACCAAGGGAAAUCUGUGGGAUUUGGGGCAGUAAGUGUGGGAAUCUGCAAAGGGACUGGACAGUGAUUUGUUUCCUUGCUUUUCAUAAAUAAUGGCCCCUAGUACCCUGAAAACACACACACAGACACAAACAGGCCAAUGAAGUAGGCACAUGUGAGAUUUGUAGGCAAUGGACAUUUCCAUCAGAAAAACCAGAGGAAAAUUUUUGAUCAGGAUUACGGGAGUGAGGCUCGAUGGCCAAGAGUGAUUAGGUUAAGGGCCAGAUGGCUUUAAAGUAUACGGAAAUGUUUUUCAAGUUUGACUUUUAUAGCAUUUAAAAGGAGGACGAUUUCUUAGAGCCUUUACAGAACUGCUAAAUUUUGAUCUGUCUAAUUUUAAAGGAAUUCAGCUGUAUGAGAAUUGCUGUUAGCUCAGAUAGGGAAGGAAUCUGGUUUCAAAUGCAGAUACAUGGAACAAAGUUUCUAGGGGUGCUUCUUCCUGAUUUAAAUAUAGCUCCCAGGCAGAAGCCUAGAUAAAUUCAGCCACAAUGAUUUAAAAUCAUAAGUACUUACAGUGGAAGUUCUUUUAGGCACUGUGCAAAGUUCUCCUGCAAAUUAUGCCAUCAACUGUUUAUUCCUCAGAACUAUACAAGAUAAAAAUCAUAAGCAUCACUUAAAACUGAUGCAAUACAGCCUUAAAUCCUUAAACUGCUAGGGAUUGCUUUUGUUUGCCUAAAAGGUAGAUCUUUCAUCACAUGAGUUGUUUAAAAACAUUUAAUUGUGGGGGUGGGAAGGGAUGUGCAUAAUUAUUUAGUUAUUUGUGUUAAUUACAUAGUAGCAUACUUGCUUGAAAUUCUUUCUUUUUUCCCCCUUUUCUUUCCAGUGAUCUCUCUUCUAACAACCUUGUUCCUGAAGAAUCAACAGUUUUUUCUUGCUGUGGGUUUAAAAAAAUUCAUUUUGUAGCCUUUUUGAGUGGGUAGUAUUGAUCCAAUCUGACACAGACUUGCAAGUGUAAACUCUUAAUACAGGAAAAACUUCAAUUCUUAAUACGGAAAGCUUGUAUUAGUUUUGUUGUUGAGCUUAAACAGUUCUGGUUGAAUGGCAUGUUGUAUAUAGAAUUCAAAACUCCAAAACCUGUUUGGUAAAUAACUAGGCAUUUGAGGUCCAAUGGCUAAUUCAAAUUAAGUUAGUUCUAUACAUGUAAGUGCACAUCCUGUUUAGACUGACACGUGGUUUGGUAAAAGAAAAAAAAUGAAUAUACACUUGGAAAGAUGCUAUCUGUGGAGUAUAUAAAUAGUAAAUAGCAAAAGAGUGAAGUUUAUACUCAGGUAUGUUGUCAUCUUUUUGGUUGUCCUCAGUGGGGGUGAGUUAUGAGUGAUAAGGAGAAUUUAAAUUUCUAAAUUUACCUUUUCCAGUUAAAGGAAUGAAUUUAAAUGCUUAAAGAAUUUUUUUUUUUUUACUUACAAAGCAAGUUUAAAAUAUGAUCUAAUGCUUACAGUAUGUACUACCUUCUUGAAAAGCUCUGUUCUUUUUCUGAGUGAUAAGUAAUCAUUGAUUUGAGGGUAUGUUCAGAUUAUAUAAAAAAGUAAAACUUACAGGACAAAAUUUAUGUUUCCUAAUCUCCUAAAAUACACUGGAUUUCAAAUAACGGAGAGUUCUAAUGUUGAAUACUGUUUAGAUUUCCAGCAGGUAUAAUUGUUGGAUAUAAUUGAUUGGCAUAACCUGGAUGAUUCACCCAAUAUCCAAUCAACUUCAGUGGUAGAGAAUGCUAUAAUUGGAGUUUUGAGAGUAACCUGGAAACUUAUUUGUCUAGGCCUGAAGUCAAAUGCAUUCCCUCAUGCACUGGUCAAAAAUUUUUAGUCUGAGAAAUGAAGAUUUAUUUUAAAGGCGAAGAAAGUGCUUGGCUGUUUCAAAUAAACUAUAUCCUGAACUUAGAUUUGUAGAUAGUUAAUGAAAUAAAAGUCCAAUUUUGUUCCAAACAUUGUUUUAAAACACCCAUUUGUAAAUUGUCUGCAUUUGGUUUUCAUAUGUUAAUGAUUUGGGAUCUGAAACUUAUUUCAGAAAGGCAUUUUGGUUUAUCUUAAAAAACACCACACAAAACUGUCUAAACAACUCUGUAAAUAAACUGUUCCAAAUGCCUCAAUUUGAUGAAUGAAUUAAAGAAUUAUGGUUCUUAAUCCAAUUAUGAUCAGUCUGGUUAUUCCAUUUCCCAUUUGGGGGAGCUUGGGGAGUUGGAAUAGUAAAUGAUUCUCAAAUGUGAGUGGGGUCUUUGUUGUUUACUUUGUGUGUGUGAUGUAACGUAAAUAAUCACUCAUACCUAAUAUUUAUGAGAGGGAUUUCUGAUGUGGAGAAGUAAUUUCAAGAUCUUAAAUUAACCAAGAGUUCGUUUGCAUGAAAAGUUGCCAUUAAUAAAGGAGUAAAGUGAAGUUUUUAAAAAUAUGAAGCAAAGAUCUAACCUUUUGCUUAAAUAUAAUGAAUUUUGAUAUUUAAGAGGGGAGAAAUGGAGUGCUUAAGGCUCAGUAGAAGGGCAGACAAUCAGGCACUUUUAGUUUGUUUUAGCCAGGCCAUAUGGGGACAUUUCUGUAGGACUAUUUAAUAAAUUUUACCAAAUUCAAUUUCCUUGUCUUUAAAAUUGAGUCAGGGUCAAAGGUAGGCUAACUAUGAGUUAGCGGAAUUUCGCGGGGGGUUGUUUCCUCCAAAGCCCUGCUCCUUUAUCUGCCUACACGGGACUUUUGAAGGCUUUACCAGCGAGGACCCUGACCUUCAGGAUGGGCCCUUGACAGUCCAUUUUGCUUUGAUGGGCCCUUCUGAAUUCCUGCCUCAUUUGCCCCAUUUAACCUCUGGCUCAUAAGCUAAUUAUUUUAAAGUUGCUAAUAGUUCAUUAUGGUUUAAUUCUCAAACUAGAUGAUAUUACUGUUAUUUUGGCAGUUUAUUAUGAUCGUCUAAUUCCAUAGAGAUAAACUUGUUGCAAUUACAGGUAUCAAGGAAAGCUGCCAGGAGGAAAUAUUUACAUGCAUGAGGACUUUUUCAGGACUACUCAAAUCAUACCUUAUAGGCAACUAAUGAUUUUACUUGCAAUUAAGGAUAACAUUCAGUAGGGGCAGCAUAUUGACAAAAUUAGGAAAAAUUUGAAUGCAUGUAAAUAACCAUUAAAUAACCAUCCUUCAAAAUUGAGCCAUAAAAAUGUAUCUUGGGGAGUACUAGUGAUGGUGGCAUUGAAUUCUACAAGUAUAAGUCCAUUCAUUUUCUAUUUCUUAAAGUUCAUUAUAAGUAAAAACAAAACACCCCAAAACAAAGACCUGAUUGUAUCUCUGAUGCUCAGCUACAUGUCAUUCAACUACUGUAUGUUUUUAUGAUAUCCUAUGUACAUAGCUUAAAAAUAAUACAGUAGUCAUAGGGAUGAGCGGACUUUAGUUUGAUACGCAGUUUGUAUUCUCUGGUAGCUUAAGACAUUUUUUCUUACUUCAACACCAAUUAAACUGUUGGAAGUGAGGGAAUUCAGGAAGGAAUCAGGAGAGGAGAAAGGCUAUCUCAUUUGUAGGUCUGUGAUUCAUCCAAAACGUUAUUUAGAGAUCUGAACUUACAGGGUUCUACCUCCUUUUUUUUCUUAACCUCUUUUUUUCUUUCUUUCUUUCUUUUUUUUUUUUUUGAAAUGAAGUCUUGCUCUGCCACCAGGCUGGAGUGCAGUGGCGCUAUGUUGGUCCACAGGCGGAGGGAUGUUGAACCCUCCGCCUCCUGGGUUCAAGGGAUUCUUGUGCCUCAGCCUCUGGAGUAGCUGGGAUUGCAGGCAUGCGCGGCCACACCCAGCUAAUUUUUGUAUUUUUAGUAGAGGUGGGGUUUCACUAUGUUGGUCAGAGUGGUCUCGAUCUCCUGACCUCGUGAUCCUCCACCUCAGCCUCCCAAAGUGCUGGGAUUACAAGCGUGAGCCACCGUGCCUGGCCUUCUUAACCUCUUAAACUGCAAAUUAUGAUGCCCUUUCUUAUAGGGGUAUUGUUUGGAUUAUGUUAGAUACUACGUGUGAAAUGCCUAGCAUAGUGUCUGUCAUGAACUAGGUGCUCAAUAAAUGUUAGCUACACUCAGCUCUCUCUCCCAGUCGAGUCUAGGUUCUGAUCAUUAAUAACGUUUGAAGUUUCAUUUUGUACUUACUUUGAACUUAUUUGAGUCUAAAAAGAAAAAAUGUAUCACUUUCUUGAGGCUGAGAUCAACACUUUAAAAUAGUGAUUCAGUGGUCUGUAUAUGAUCUCUGACAAUGUGGUUUUAUUAAGGUGCUGUAUUUGGUGCAAGUGUGAAUUCUAUCUUUUAUUCAUAUAAGUGCUCCUUCAGUAAUUAACAUUUUUACCCUACAUAAUAGGUAAGGAUAAAUAAAAACUUUAGGACCUAAUUCUGUAGAUUUUUCCUCUUGUUAUCUUUUUGAUUUCCUGUUAGCAAAUAUGAACUAGUGAAAAUUUAUUGAGAUUUAAUCGUUUGAUAGUCAUUCACCUCUGCAUUAUAUUAAGUUAUAGUACCUGUGGAUAAACAGAAAGUCCGUGUGGAAAAAGAAAUCCAUCUGAGUUUUCAAUGUUUUGCUCUCUGGAGUCAACAGUCCUUCAAAGAGAAACUUGUAGGUUGGUUUGUUUAUUUAAAUUGGGUGCAAGGAGAAAGGCACCAUAAACAUACCAUUGCCUGAUUUGAAGAGGUGAUGUAAAGUAACAUGGAGAAAUUAGUUGUUAUUUUCUCUUCCCAAUGAAACAGAAUUUGUCUAUCAGUACAACUAAGCAAAGAUAAAGGAAAGUCUUCUUAAAACAGAAAAUAAAUGUAUUUUCUUGCAUUAAUUGGGGUUCCUGAAGAAGCAGUUGCCAAGAUGGGAUUAGACCUGUAAGAAGUUUAUUAGGGGAGAGGGCAGGACAAGGCCGGGAGAGCCUUUUGACUAUGAGGCAAGUUUGACACUUAUGCAAGGAGAGGGGCAAGGGAAGACGAUUGAGUAGGAAGAAGCUUGACUAUAGUGCAGCCUAUGAAAGGUUUGGCUAGGCAAAUAAGAGUCAGCCAUUGGAAGAGUCACCUAUCUUGAAAGAAUGGCCUGUAUCAGCAUUCCUCACUGUCAGUCAUUGGCUGGGAGCAGCUACAGGAAGCAUGGCCUCCGUGCCUAAGUGGUGCUAGAGCCAUAGGGGAAGCAGUUGGGGAAGUAAGUCAGUUACACUCUCAAAACAGGAGAUCUGAAUGGUAUAGCUGUGGUUUGGCAGUAUAGCCCAGUUUAGUAGUACUUCACUUGCUUUGGACACUUGCUUUGGACUCUGUCUUUUUCUGUCUCUCUGUCACACACACACACUCACACACAUGAGACCUGGCAAUUUCUUUGAGGUCUCUUUGAGUUUUGAGUUUCUUUGAGCUUUGUUUUCCUCAAUUGCAAAAUGAGUGUAAUGGCAGUAUCACCUCACUAAUUGGGAUUAAAUUAGGUUAUACGAGAUCAUCUCUAAGUCCAUUGUACUGUUUGUGGCAUGGAGGAAAUGCCCGAUGUAUUUUACACUCUUUUCGAUGUACUCACAAAAUGCAUCUGAAAGCUAUAGAUGAAUUUUAUCAGGUGAUUGUAAAUAUAUUUAAAUAAUGGAUAUUUCAUAUAAUUGGAAGGCAUUGUUUAUGCAAGCAAACAUCUUUAAUGCUUAUCAUUUAAAAAUAGCUUGGUUCAUUUAUCUUCCAUUAAUCCUUAUUUUUUAUCAGAGUAUAAACCGUACACCAGCUAUACCAACUGACCUUGACCAUCUUUAGGUAAUUGGCCCUAAAGCAUGAGGCAGAACUCUCUUCAUUUCCUUACCUCUCUAGGCUUUCUAUUCAGUUGAGUAGCAACGCACUGGAAGUCUGCAUUUUAUCUUGAGCCUCAAACACCUUGCAAGUCUUUGCUCCCCUGUGUUACUGUUCCUAAACCAACUUGCAGCACCACAAAGCACUGAACUCAAGUGGCCCUCAGCGCGAGCUCCUGCUGUGAUGAGUCGCAGAGCCACCAGCACUUUGUUGCCUUAGAUUUGAUCACUGCCAUGAGCAGUCCUUCGAUUGUCAGCUAAGAGCCCCUUCAGGGAGUUGUCCCUUAAUAGAAAGUCUCUUUUCUUCCCUCCUGUUGUAACUUUAAAUUAAAAGAAACUGUAGAGGAGCUGGUGGCAUUGCAGUAGUUCAUUCUUCUACCCACUGGGAGAACAACAUCUGAGAAAAGACGUUAUUGGACUGAGAAUUGAGUUGUUGCUAUUUUUUUGGGCCAGAGUCGGCGGGGAGGCGGUUGUGGUGGAGGAUGAAGACCACGUCAUUUAGACUCAGUCAGACUGGUAAUCAGGAUUGUGAUUGAGAGCAAUACUUUUGUGUAUGCAAGGAAGCUUUCUUUUUGGAUACAAGAAGACGCCCACUUAGCCUGUGAGUUUCAGUAGGAUUCCUGGGACCCCUAAUAUUUUGACCCAGAUUUUUAGGUGGUUCUCUGUGUUGUACUGUGGGAAACUGGCACUGGGACAACUUUGGAAUCCAAGGAGGAUGGGAGGCAGGAAAAGAGAGCUAAUUUUUGACACAUUCCUCAGACAAGGGACUCCUCUAGGGAAUCUGUGCCCAGGAUAAGGACUGCUUACUGUGAAGCUUUUGGCAUAAUUUUUUCCUGAAGAGUGAGCACGGGUUGCUUCAAUGUCUCUACUUAAAAAGACUGACAAACUUACGUUUGUGAGAGGAAAAGAAAAAGAUGUUCAUACUUUUGACAGUGUGUUUCCUAGAUGGCACCUCUCACUAAACUUUGGAUUUAAUCCUCCAUUGUGGCAGGUUUAUACCUUCCAUAGUUGCUGGCUCAUCCCCAUUCUGGUUUAGGAACUAUGGCAAAAUCCGAUGUCUGCCUAGAUGUACCGGUGUAAUUCAGGACUACUAAGAGCUGACGUUGUUUGAUGUAUACUAUCAGGAGUAGACUGCAGUUUGCAUGCAAGUUCUUGUGAUGCUUGAUAUUCCUGUGCACCAUUGGCAUUCUUUCAUAUGUGUCUGGCAGAAUCAGUCUCAUCAAUGUACUCUUGCACUGGGAACUGCUUUUGAAGACAUGCAUACUAUUUCUUAUAAUUCUGUCUUGAAUUUUCUUACUUCACUCUCAGCCUCAUCUCCACGUACCUUCUCUAUUAACCGAAUAGGAGUGUCUUUUCCACAUCCAACCAGGAACUAAAGUGAUAAUUUUCAUGCAUAUGAAACAAACAGAUAGAGAUCUAUCAGCAUGUAAAGAAAUUUCAUAGGUCCUCUAUUUAUUUUUAGAGACUUCCUGGGGCCACCCAGAAGCUCUUCUCUUCCUAUCUCCUUUUACCUAUCACUCCUUGCUGGCUUUUCUUAACCUUUCUCUUACCACAAAUUCUCUAUUCUCAUGGCACCACUGUCCACUCUGCCUUGUGUUGGACUCACUGCAUGAAAUGAAAGGUUUUCGAAAUACUCUGCUGCCUGAUUUGAAAUGGGUAACCAUAGGGUGACAUAAAACAUUUCCAAUUAGAAGGUAAGCUCCCUGAGGGCAUUGAAUUGUAGUCCUAGCAGAAUCACAAUGCCUGAAACAGAGCAGCAACCACAUACAUGAUUGCUGAGUGAGCAUAGUUUGCAAGAUGAGUUUCAUAUUGAGUCAAGGCAGCCCUGCACGAUGGGGAAGUAGGAAAACGAACAGCUCUUGAGUGUUUACUGUGUUCCAGGAGGGGUGCUAGAUGCCAUACAUGGAUAAUCUCAUUUAACCCUCCCAGCCCUCCUAUCAGAUGGAUAUUAGCACCUUUUCACAGAUGAACAAGAGACUCCAGUGGUCAAGUGACUUGCCCAUCUUCCUCAGCUCUAGUGAGCGGGACAGUCUUUGCCUGAAUUUCAGUCUAUUUGAUUCUGCCACUUUUAUUCUCUUCCAUCACAAGGUGUUGGUGUGGGAUUCCUCUCUGUAAAAUGGGAGCACUAACAAUACCUGGCUAUCACGAGACAGUUAGGAGGAAGAGAUGAGAAAUAGUUAUUGAAAGCUAUGUCUUUGCUGUAAAGUGAUCUCUUUCUUGUUUUUAUACUUUUUCUUAUUUUUUGAGACAAGUUCUCACUCUGUUACCCAGGCUGGAGUGCAGUGGCACAAUCAUGGCUCACUGCAGCCUCAACUGCCCGAGCUCAAGUGAUCCUCCUACCUCGGCCUCCUGAGUAGCUGGGACCACAGGCAUGCGCCAGCAUGCCCAGCUAAUUUGCUUUAAAUUUUGGGUAGAGAUGGAGUUUGUUUUAAAUUUUGUGUAGAGGUGGGGUUUCAUCAUGUUGCCCAGGCUGGUCUUGAACUCCCGAGCUGAAGUGAUCUGCCUGCCUUGGCCUCCCAAAGUGUUGGGAUUACAGGCGUGAGCCACUGUACCCAGCCUAUAAAGCGAUUUCUAAAUGUUGCUUAUUAUCAAAUAUUCACUAAUCCCUAUAUUCACCAAAAAAUAUUCAUUGAACACACAGAUGCGUGUUGCAUAUACUUAAGGGAAAGUAUUUUAUGACUUAAGCAGAGAUUCUGAAUACGUAAAAACUGACAUCAAAGGAAAUUACAGAACAGUGUUUCUCAAAGGUGAUCAUCCAGUCAGCCAGUUGAAAACCACUUGGGAUAUUUGUUGAAAAUGGGGCUUUCUGGGUCUCAUCCCAGACAUAUAGAACCUGAAUCUCUGUAGGUGUAGUGCUGUAACCCUGCAUUUGUAACAAGUGUGACUGGUGAUUCUUUUGCACAUAAAAGUUUGAGAACCAGUGAUAAAAAAUUCAUUGAUCUAGUUUGGUAGUAAGUUAUAUAUACAUGGCAUAUGGAAUUUAAGUAAGAUGCUCACAGAAUAGUGGUAGUGCCAAGAUAAAGCACAACUGAUUGUUGGACUGCUAGAAAGACUUUUUUUUUGAUAAUGUGGUUUUAGGAGUUCUAAAAUAAAAUUUAAAGAGCCUUUAGUAAUUUGAGUAUAUAAAACAUUAACAUGCUUCAAGUCAAGAGUGAGGGGACCUGACAUAAGGAAUCUAGGGGUUGGGGAGUGGGGAAGGGGGCCCUGGGGCCAGUUAUAUGUAUUCUAGCCUUGGAAAUAACUUUUUAACAGGCCAGACUGAAGGAGACUAAGUAGACAGAAGACAAGAGGUUGAUCUAUUUAUCCAGUCCUGUAUCCCAAAUAAGACAAUGUCUGGGACAUAGUGGGUGCCUAAAGAUGUUUGUUUAAUCAAUGAAUAAAAACACACAGAAGGAGAGAGCAGCAUGUAGAAAACAGACUAGAAGAGUUUGAUUAUGAUUACUAUGGCUAGAGAAGGGGAGAAAGAGUAGGCUGAAAAGGAGUCCUGGUGAGAUAAGACGAGGACAGGGUUUUAAUUAGGCUAAUAUGGUCCUUACAGGAAAGUGCCUUUUAUACAAACAAAUAAACAAUGAAAAACACUAACCCAAGGUUUGUAUGGGAUCAAAACAUGAGUCCUCUGUGUCUAUUAUCUUGGGAUAACAGUUACCGCAUGAGGAUAGGGACCUUGUCUAUUUGUUCUCCGUGUGAUCUGUUUUGUUCUCCGUAUGAUUGUAGCACUCAGCAAAUAUUUAUUGAACAAACGACAGCGCUUCCACAUGGACAGGGGAAAAAAGCAUUUACGUUAUACAAAAAUAUCUUGUAAAGAGAGAAGCUAAAUCUUUACAGAUGCUAGCCAAUAGACUGGUGAUCGUGAAAAUAAUAAAUCUUCAUAAAACUGCACAUUCUUAGACAAUCUAUUUAACGUUCAGUGAGGUCUACAUCUGAUUGUCUGUCACCAAGCAGUGCUUUAUGGACAAUUCCACUUUCAUUUUACUGUUAUGAAAAUCCACCAGCGUGCCCAGCACAGUGUCUUGCUAAUAUUAGCUAUUUAAUAAGUAUUUGGUGAAUAAUUCAAUGAAUGAAUGAGGAGUAUUGGUUUGGGGCUGGGGGGAGAUGGGAACUUGAAAGCAGCCUGAAAAGAGAGUUGCCCUCAUUCAGUUAGAAUUCCCAGAGUGACAUGCGAUCCAGAGAUCUUUAAGCAGGCAGAUUUCCCAUACAGGUCAAGGCCUGGUUAUUGGAAUCUUGAGGGGAAGAAUGUUUGCUAAGGUAAUGACUGCAAAAGUGGGUUCAGCAUUGUUGGAAGAGGCAACUACUCAUUUGAUCUGAAAAAUAUAUUCAGGGGGAGGGAAGGUAAAAAGUAAUUCUAAACCUAACCAGAGUUUUAGUAGAAAAAUGGCUGUAAUUCAAGCAGUGUAAUGUUAACAUCAAUGCGUGUCUCAUGGCUCAAGCCCUGCAUACUGCUUUGGAAAUAAAAGGAGAUUGUGUAAAGAAUUAGCAAUACAAGGCAUUUUUAAGUGCUUUAUUGCAAAGGCCUGUGAUACUCUGUGAAAUCUAUGCAGCCUCUUUCUUCCUGCUGUGCUUAAUUUCAGAAUCUGAUGCUAUUACCUAUCCUUGGAGGAAAAAGAAAUAAUCAUUCUCUGUUAACUCUUAAAAAUCAAGUUUAACUUUGCACUUAUUUUCAACAUAAUCUUUCCGAUAUUUCUUCAGAAGAGAGAAGUGGAGUAUUUAGCCAUGGAGGUUAGUAUCUAGGAUUGCUUCUGGGGGCAGGGUUAGAAUAAGAGGGCAAGUUGGAAAUAAAUGUUGCAGGCAAAAGUUUAGAAAUGGCUCCAUCUGUUUGAAGGAUGAGGUCUCUAAAAGGGUCAUCAGAGAUUGUGUUUGGCAUGAGUCCAGAGCAGAAGCUAGAAAGGUAAAUGGGUUAUAAGGAAGAUCCAGCAGAAGCCAGGACAGGAAUUAACAACAUAGGUGGCUAUCUUCUUAUGACAUGAAGACCUGUCCACCAAGAAUCGUUUCCUCCCUGGUAUACCAUCAUGGCGCCCCUGCUCCUGUCUCACUUGAAAGCACAGUUGACACUGAUGUUGAUUGAUGUUAUUGUUGCUAGACAUUGUACUAAGCAGUUUAUUUUUAUUGAAUUUUCCUAAUAACUCUAACAUAGUUACAGAUGCUGUCCCAUUAUACAGCCAAGGAAACUGAGCUUGCUCAAAGUAGCAUAGCUAGCAAACGGCAUAGCUGAAACUUGAACCCAGAGUGGACUGAUUCUGAAGUCUGAGCUCUUGCUCAUUGUAACAUAGAAAAAUAUAUUUUUAGUCCUGUUAAGUCAUCCCUCAAAAUGAUGCUUGCAUUUUCCCCUUUCUUCUAUAUUCACCCCUCUCACCCUGAAUCAUUGCAAGUUCCCCAAACUAGUAUCUUUCCCUCGACUCUGCUCUAUUUACCACUAUCAGGCCAAUCCUCCUGACAUGCUGUUAAUAUUUAGAAAUAUUUCUCCAACAUUCAGAGUGCCUGGGUACCACACAUGGAUGCGACUAAGAUUCUUAAGUCUGGUUUCUAAGAGCUUCUUCAAUGUCUCCAACUAUCUUUUCAGGCUCAUGUUUGAGACCUUCCUUUCAAGAAUAAUUUGCUUGUGAUCUGGUUCAAGCUGAACAGAGAUUUUCAGAUGACUCCCAAACUAUCUGCAACACAUCAGCCCUAUUAACUCUUCUCAGAAUGCUCAUACAGAAGCCAUGCCAGUGCACAAAAGCCACUUCUGACACCUGGCCCUGUCUGACUCAUGGAUUUCUUCCAGGAUUGCUCUUUCUAUCUGCUUUAAACCUCCUUGUCAAUUGACUUUCCUUGGCUCCCAAUCCACUUUGCUCUGUAUUUUUGCUUUCUCUUUUUGUUUUGUUUCUUCAUUCAUUCAGUAAUCAAUAAAUAUUUCUGGAGUGCCUACUAUGAGCCAGACACCAUGUUAACUGCUAGAGAUUCAGUGGUGUGUGGAACAGGCACACACUUUGCACACAAGCAAUUAAAGUCUAUUAGGGAAGAUCAACAUUAAUCAAAUAAUUAUCAGCGUUUAUGAUUGCAAAUUGUGGAACUGUAUUUCACAGAAGAUUAUACAGCAUAUGAGAGAAGUUUCUGAUGUAUUUGAGGGAGGAGCAGUUAGAGGAUGCUUACAUGAAAAUGUCACAUUUUAAAGAUGGCUAAUGAGGUAAUGAGGACAGGAGAAAAAAAUCUUUCAAGGUGAAAGGAAUAGCAUGUGUAAGGUUUCCAAAGAGGGAGGGAAAAGAGUGUGUUCUUAGAAUUAGAAGGGCAGCAUGGCUGAAGCAGAGUGGAAGGGAAAUAGAUGGAGAUGAGGUUGUAGAGAGAGAUUGGGAUCAGAUCAUUAAGCUUUUUCAGCUAUGUUACAGAGUUGAGUCUUCAUAAUAACGGUGAUGAAGAACCCAUUGAGGUUUCUCAGGACAAUAAAAUUUGUGCCUACAGCCUGUAGAUCACAUUUAAGAGAGGCAGGAAUGAACGGAUUUGGGUGAGCUAGAAAGGAGGCUAUUGAAAUGAUUCACACAAGAGAAACAUGGUGGCUUGGACUAUAGCAGUAGUGUUAGAGAGGAAGGCAAGAGGAAGGAUUUCAGAAACAAACAUGCUGUUUCAGAUGCUUUGUACCACCCUCCAUCCCCAUUCCACUAACCUAUUGGGAUACUCCCUCUGGUCAUCUCCCAGUGUUUCCAUGUUUCACAGCUUUAAAAAGUAGGUGCUUAAAUCCAUACUUCUAGUUCCUGGGGACUCUGCUGGUGGGGAGAAAUUUGACACAGAACAUGUAGUGCCUCGUGUCUACAUAUACAUACUUGCCUUCACCUCUUUAUGUCUUCCUUUUGUACAACGCUUCUCCCUCGUACAGAUAUUCUAAAAUCCUGCCCAUCCCUUAAUUUCCAAAUUACAUUUUACUCUUUCACAGCAUUCUCACCAAAUAUACUAGCUGAAUAUCUCUCACUCUGAUCUUAUGACACUUAUAUCUGUAACUAUCUUUAUGGCUUUCAGCAUCUAUUGUAGCAUAUUGUAAUCAUGUUGUGAGCAUGUCUUAUCUCCUGAGAGAUAUUGUGAGUUUGUGUCAAGGGACAUCGAUGCUGUAGCUCAAUAUUAACACUGCUAUUUUGGAUUUUCCCUUCUAGCUGGGUUAUUUACUUGAGCCCUCUGAGUCUGAUUCCUCAUCUGCAGAAUGGGUAUAAUUACAUUUACUUUAUGAAGCCAUUAUGAGGAAUUAAUGAUAGAAUGAAUGCAAGGUACUUAAAAAAAUCUCCGGCACAUAAUGAAUCUCAGCAUACAAUAGCAGUUUAUGGUUAUAAACUUUAUUCUUUGAAGUCAGAACCCUGUGUCUUAUUACUACUUUUCUCUACUUGUAACUCAGUGAAUAUUUGUUGAAUUCAGAUUUGAAUUUAAGUCUCAUUUCUGCCAGGGGAUACGAACACUGUAUAAAUAAAUUUUGAUACUUGUCUGUGAGAACUUCAAGUUGAUAGGGGAGCUAGUAACAGAAACUGGUUAUUUGUUAUUGGGAUAAGUAUAGUGAUAGAGAAAUAAACCCAGAUAGAGUAUUUUGAGAGCACCGAAGAGAGGUUGGAGAAGGUUUUCUAAGACAACUUAUGCCUGAGCUGAGUAUUUUAUUAAUCAAUUAGAUACCAUUAAAAUAAUGUAUGCACAUAAUAUAAAACCCAAGGCUAUAUAAUAAAAUAGCAUUUUUGUCCUAUUGACAACUAUACCCACUCCAUUUCUACUGCUUUCAAUUCUGUGUUUCUAAGUAAAAUGUUUAUUCCUUGUUUUCCUUGUUUAAAAAAAUGUUAGAUAGGCCGGGCGCGGUGGCUCACGCCUGUAAUCCCAGCACUUUGGGAGGCCGAGGCGGGUGGAUCAUGAGGUCAGGAGAUCGAGACCAUCCUGGCUAACAAGGUGAAACCCCGUCUCUACUAAAAAUACAAAAAAUUAGCCGGGCGCGGUGGCGGGCGCCUGUAGUCCCAGCUACUCGGGAGGCUGAGGCAGGAGAAUGGCGUGAACCCGGGAAGCGGAGCUUGCAUUGAGCCGAGAUUGCGCCACUGCAGUCCGCAGUCCGGCCUGGGCGACAGAGCGAGACUCCGUCUCAAAAAAAAAAAAAAAAAAAAAAAAUGUUAGAUAUCAGUUGACUUCUCACUAUUUGGCUCUCUUAUACUAUACUCCUCCUACCCCUACUUCCUAAAACCACACAUUUUUUUUCUCCUAUUGUUCCAAUAUAAUUUCUUUUUUUGUUGUUAAAUCAGUUUAGUAAUACAGUUACUUUGACUAUGUAAAUGUUGCGUGUGUCUUCCUGAGCAUAUUAUAUACUGAUUACUUUGACUUUUUAAAUACAACUUAUUUUGUUUCCUGGAGCUAAUAAUGGCCUAUGUCCAAGCCUUCCAAAGUUUUACUGGAAGUUCUCAGUGUUUACUGGAAUUCCUGAGCCAUGGUUUACUGGGUAUGUGGCAUAUCCAGGGCGGGCCCUGGGGGAAGUCAACCCUACUGCAAGGACCAUUUUAUUACUGGUAGAAUUUACAGUUGUUGGAUCUAGGUGAUAAAAGGCUCACCAACUUUUUAUCAGUUAUAUUUCUUAGAUUUUCUGCCAACAGAGCACCCACUUAUUAUUUGCCCUUGGAUGUUCUGCUUCCACCAACCUGUCCUUGCUAAGACUGUGAGUUCAGCUAAGCAAGGCAAGGGGUGGUGCUCUGAGAGAGUGGUAGUGUGUUCCAAGAAGAUGGGACAACCUGAGUGGAAAGGCAUGGCAGUGAGAGAUAGCAUGUUGUGUUCUUGGAAUUACAGAUAGUUUGGUAUAGGUAGAGCGUAGAGUACAGGGCAGGACUAGCCGAGAUGAGGCUGUGUGGUGGGCAGGAGUCAGAUCAAGGUGAUCUUUUUAUUACAGACUCAUACUCACUAGAUUCUGUCGUGUAGGCCAUGGGGAAACUCAUACUGUUAAGUAACAUGGUCUGCUUUGCUUGUGAAUGAAUGACAGAGUAAGCAAAAAAUGGAAAACUAGCUCCUGAAGUCAGCAGUUAAAAUGCUGUCUUUGCAUAUUCAGUGAUGUAUUAAUAUUUUAGGGAUACUCCAUCAGGCAAAUUGUUAGAGCACACAUCCCCAAGAAUACACACACAAGCACAGAAACACACAGACAUUCAUAGUUUAUGUACAUGUGUUGCUACUUUAGUUAAUAUUCAGGGCCCAAUAAACACUGAAAGCAAGGUCCAGGUUAAACGAUGGUGCCUCUAACAGUCAUGUCAGAGUUUCCCGGAGACCUACUGUGACAUGUAGAUUUGCAUGCAGUGAGUUUCUGGGAGGAUUCUCAGGGACACCACCUGCGAGAGGGUGAGGGAAAAGGACGGAUAGGAGGAGAUGUUGACUGUGAUGCAGCUGAGGCUUCAGCUCGCCAAUGGGGAGCUCUGGAACUGGAUGGCUGUUCAGAGAUGUUCUGAACGGAGACCCAGAGCCAGGCCUUUAUAACUGAACAUCGGGGUGGGAUGUGGGCCAUCCCUGUGGAGGGGCCACAACUCUAAGCUAGGGCUAUUCUUGGAAAGGGACUGAACUGGGAGCUUCCAGCAGCCGAUACUCCUGGCAGCUGGGAGAGCAAGUGCCGCUGGGCAGCGCACCACAGCAUCCACUACAAACAACCUUUCUGAUAACUUCUCUAUUUUUUAGAAUUCUCAGAUUUUUAUUAAAAUGCGGAUGCCAAAGAACUAGCAAUUGGUCCAUGAGAUGCAAUUCUGCCAUUUUCCUGGGUUUACUUAUGUUUGCGUUAUUCGUAUUACUUGAAAAUCUGUCGAUUUUUUUUUUUGAGAAGAAAACCUUUUUAAACCCCUUGUCCAUUUUAUGAGGGUCAAUUUAGCUAAAAAUUAGACAAGGCAAUCCAUAAUGCAUUUCCUCAAGCACAGGAAAACUGUUAUGUGUGACAAAAUGGUGAAACAAGAGAGAGGAGAGCAUUAACAUUAACUUCUUCCUGUUGUGAAAAUGAGGGCCCCCAUGUCAGUUUAUUAGUAAUUGGAUUAACAAAUACAACCUUGUAGAUCAUCUUGAAUUUCUGGCUUUGGAGAAAAUGUCUUUGUGGAAUGAAACCAAGGCAACAUUUUAACUGGAGGUAGGACAGCUUGUUGGACCUACACAUAUGGUGGUGGUGAUGGGGUCUCUUUAUGUACGGGGUAUAGUGUUGCUCAGUACGUGGACAAGAGGUAAUCAGCCAGAAAGGGUAGUCCUAGGUUUUUUCAGGUUCCCAGGUGGACGUCUAAGUCAGUGCUCUCCUAAUUUUUCUGAUCAUGUAUAUAAACCGUCAAUAAAAAAUAUAUUACUCUAUUUAAACAGUAAACACACAGAAAGGGGAUAAGAUAAAGAGUAAAUAAAGAAUAUCUAUAAAAUCAGAAACGUAAUUAGAAGCUGUAAUAUUUUCUUCUAACAUGCCAGUUGACUUUUUCUUCUUUUUGCACCCACUUCAAAUACUACUGAAUUAGAUUUCUAAAGCAUAAGUUAUGUACCAAAUGGGGACAAAGUGCGUUGGAGACAGAAUUUGGCAAUUUAAUGGGUUUGACAUGUGCUACUAUUUAAAUGAGGUAGUAUGAGCUCCAAGUAUUAAAAAGUGAACUGAAGAAAAAUUAGGUUUUAGAAUAGAAUUGGGAUGCUUUAAAAUAUUUUUUUAAAUCAUGGAGGGAAUGUGUGUGUGUAUGCAUGUGAGUGUAUAUCUGUGUGUGUGUUUGCAUUAGCCAGGGUCAUAAUGACUUAGCAUUUCUUUCUGUUUAGCAAUUCCCCACAAUUAACUAAAAGGUUGGGGCCACACUGACACCAUUACCCUUCUGUAUAUCUGGCUCUAAUUUAUGAUCCAUAUCCUGCCUUAUAUCCCAGAAUGCUUUUGAAUGUUCUUCCAUUGUUUCUUUUUUUCAGAUUUAUCAAUGUAUAGAUCAGUUAAAUGCAAUAAUGAAAAGAUAUCUUUAUUAGUGUCAUCUCAGCAAUAGAAAAACUGAAAACACAAUACCUUCCAUAUGUAUAAUAAGUUCUUACCCAUCUUUUUGGAAUUUUAAAUAUUUAUAAGCACUUUCCUGGUAAAACUCAGACGAGUUUAUAAGAAUUAUCCUAGAGUCAUCUUGUGCCUGAACUUAAGAUAGCUUCCUUAUUAAAAUCUUUUAUUUUGCUAAUAAAAAUCCAUUUCAAUUAUGUUCUCUUGUUUUUAUAUUUAACAGUACCUGCUCAUGAGAUACUGGUUGCUUUAAAUUUCUUGGAAGAAAGGGGAUAAAUACAUUUCGGGUAGCAUUAUUAUUACUUUUCAUUAUGGAUAAAAUUAAAAGGUAGCUGGAUUUGGAACCAGUAUAUAGAUGUCUUAAUAAGGAUAUGGUAAUCAUGGUUCAGUCCCUAAGGAAACCUAAUCACAUAAUCUUAAAUAUAGUUCAUAAGUUAAAAGGCAGAACCUUGUUAUGCUAGUGUGCUAUCUUUAAAAUAAUAAAAUUAAGAUUCUUUAAAAAUAUACGUACAAAUGAUCUUUCCAUUAUUGAGUGUAGACUGUCUCUCAAAAGAAUAUUAUGACUUGAAAUGUUCAAGUAACUCCAUCCUUACUUGUUGUUAAUUGCUUUAUAACUAUUUGCAUUUGCAUACUGAUUUUUAAAAACUUUUUUGAGCCAGGGUCUCACUCUGUCACCCAGGCUGGAGUGCAGUGGCAUAAUCUCAGUUCACUGCAAACUCUGCCUCCUGGGUCCAAGUGAUUCUCCCACCUCAGCCUCCUGAGUAGCUGAGACCACACACGCGUACCACCAUGCCUGGCUAGCUUUUGUAUUUUUUGGUAGAGAUGGAGUUUCACCAUGUUGGCCAGGCUGGUCUGGAACUCCUGAUGUCAAGUGAUCCUCCUGCCUCGGCCUCCCGAAGUGCUCGGAUUACAGGUGUGAGCCACCAUGCCCAGCCACAUAUUGAUCUUCAUAGUAAUUUAAAAUAAACAGCGUUGUAUUUGAUUAAUCUUAACUUCUUAUUCAUUCAUUUAAACCUUUUUUAUUGAAAGUCCAUUUUUGGUUACACAUGAAUUGAGUAAGGGGGUUACAAUGGUAAGCAGAAGAGAUUUGGUCCUUACCCUUACGGAGCUUCCAGUCUAAUGAGGAAGAUGGAGGUGAGUCAGCUGACCAUACCAAUAGACUAGAGAGAUGCUCUCUCCUCCAGUGUUGUUGUGAGUGGUAGCUGGACUGUUCAUUCUUUUAAAAAUCACAAAUGCAUAGAAUCUUAAAUAAAUGCUGUUUACAUUAAACAUUUUAGUAUAUUUAACAUGUGUGCUUUAUUAAUUUAUCAAUGUUUCAUUGUUCAUCAGUGUUUAUCAAUUUGCCAAUUAAUUGGUAUAGAACUCAGACUUAAGUAUGGGUGUCCUGAGUGAAGACUCAUUAUCUUCUUGGGUAAGCCACACCAAAAUAUAUAUUGAAUGCUUCUUAGUUUUGAUUUAUUAAAAAUGGAGGAGACCUUGAAGGCAUUUGGCAAGCAAUCUAAGUGCAGAAUUUUCUAGUUUUAAAACAUUUUCAUCCCAGUGUUACGAAGGUGACAACUAAUAUAGUGGUUCUUAUAAACAAUUUGCCUUUCGUCUUUACAAAGCAUUCAAUUUGGUGUCAAUAAAACAUUCAUUUUUGCCCUUAUAUUUCCCUAAUUAUGUCAUAUUUAGUUAAUUUUCAUGAUUACAAUAACAAAUGACAUAAGCAGACUUGGGAUGAAGCAGACAAUUAAAGUGGUGAGAGCAGGAUGGUGUGGGUUACUAGAGGAGUCUUUCUGCCAUUCAGGUGCCAGGUAGGCCUAUCGUAUAUUUUGCAGAAGAAAUGGAGCACAUUAGUUUCUCAGGCGACUUGGGGAAUGUAGGUGGGCUAAGAACGUUGUAUUAUAAAUAUGUAUAGUGAUAAGUGCUAUCGAGUGUAUUAUCGAGGAAAAGUACAGGCAGCUGUAAGGAUACAUAGAGUAGCCUGUUUUAUUCUGAAAGUCCCAGAAGGCUUUCAUGAGGAAGAGCCAUUUGGGCUAUGGUAUGAAAAGCACUAAGGGCCAACUAGGUGGAGAAGUUGUGGGUGAGUAAGCAUAGAGAACAGCACGUACAAAUCUCUGCAAUGGGCUAAAGCUUGGACUGUUAAGGGAUCAAGAGAGCAGUGUGGCCAGGGCACAGAAAAGAAGGGCCAAGGCUGUGAAGGUUGAGGUUGGAGGAGGCAGGGGUCAUAUAUCAUAGAAUCUUGUAGGUCCUCUUAAGCCUUUGGGUUUUUAAUCAUAAAAGCAUUGGAGAGUAAUUAAAAGAUUCAAAAUUAUGAUUUAAAAAGAUUAUUCUGGCUGUUGUUUGGAAAAAAGAAUGAAGGGACAUCAGGUAGUGAUCCUAGUAGCCUAAGUAAGAAAUGUUGUCCUUAUUCUGAAAACUAUUCACUGUACUGUUUUUCGUGGCCUGCUACGUGACUAAAUGGGUCUUUGAAAUACUUGAGGAAAAGCAGAGCCUAAAUUUAUCGUAGUUUAAAUUUUUUUAUCACCUAGGAAGACCUGGAACAGAAUUUUCUAUACUAUACUCUUACUUACCAUUUUCUCCUUUUACAUUUAUGUUCACUGUUUCAGCACGUUAUGUUCUCAAAACAAUAGGGGAAAAAAGGAAAAGUCAUUCUUUUAAGCUUGUACCAUGCUAUUGACUUUCUUUGAAAGGACAACAAGUGUGUUUAUUUUAUCCCUGUGAGUCUAAAAAUUAACCAUGAAACAUCCUUCUUUACUUCUAAACUAUGUGUAACAAAGAAAUGCUUUAUUGCAAUUUCAUCAAUAAUUCAAAUGCAACUUAAAGGAAAGUAGGGCAGCUAAGGAAAAAUAGCACACUUGUUCCAUAAUUGAGUCGAUUAAAUAGUAUUGAGUCCCAUUGUCAUAGUCAUAUUGAUGAAACAACUUUUGUAACUACAAAAAGUCUAAUAAGAAAUAAAACCUUAGAAUGAUGAUGCAAUGUCAUGGACAUUUCUUCGUUUAUUUUCUAUUGUAAAAUACAAAUAAUGAAAGCAACCUUUUACCGAAGUGCAAUAAUAAAGGAGCAGCUUUUGAAAGGUGCUCUCAUCAGGAUAUUAGUAGUUUUCAAGGCUGUGCAGUAAUAGCCCAGGCUAUUUUGGAACUGUGCAUACAUUAGUGUUCUGGUGCAGCAUGAUACAAUAAUGUGUGAAAAAGUAUAAGCUCGCACCUUGUUUAAAUUUGCAGUUUUUGUGCAUAAUCCCACAGUGAGCUCUUGCCAGAUUUUGACUGUUUAUAGGAGAGAAAAGUUUAUAGAAGCCUACAGACUGGGGCUUGUUGUAAAUAUCUGACAAUGAAAAUAGGGUUUUAAAAAAUUGCAUGCCAUAUUUUUUGAAAGAUUAAAAGGGUUAUGUUAAGUUUAUAUUAUAUAUGAUAUUUUGCAAUGCAACUUAUGGUUAGUUUCACCCAAUGGAAGCUUCAGAAUACACAUACAUAGCCAUCUACAGGAAAAAUGUAGAUUUGCUCUAUUUAAUAUUUGCAGGGUAUGAUUGCAAAGUACAGAGUUUGAUUUUUGAAAACAACGAUUGCACUAUAAUUUAUGCAUUCAUAUUAAUGUUGUUUUCAAAAUUGUCACCCAGAGAAGCAAAACCCCUUUUCCAAUGAUGCCAUUGUUCAAAACAUUUUGGAAAAACUUCCUCUCUCGAAAUUGUCUUUUGAAUCAUUUGCAAGCCUGACUAAAACAUCCAUCUCAUUACUUUCUAAUCGCAUUUUAUACCAAGAUUCAUCAUCCUUUUUUAAUUCACCAGAAUUGGCUAUAAAUGUCUCUCUGAAAUGAUGAAAAUGGCUAAAAUUGACUUUCAAAUUAUGAAAUUUGUCACCAUUGAGGAUAUUUAGAAGUGUGUGUGCUUGCAUAUGUGUGCACAGACUUAGAAAACAGUUUCAGAUGGAGAGAAAAAUACUGUGAAUAAUGGCUGAUCUUUAAGUGAGUAGUGUUCUAAGGUGACCAUUAACAUGGUAAAAUACAUUUGAACUUAGAUGACAAGGUAUGUUUGUUUAAAAAAGUCACAUUACCUUGCAUUAGUUUUUACAACGUAUACAAAGAAAAAUGCGAAUAUGUCUUUUGGAAUGCAAGGCCAAAUACCUUACAUAAUUAGCAGUAUAUUUUAUUAUUAAAACAAAGGAUUAAGUAACUACAAUGCUAAUCCUAUGUUGGCAGAUUCUUCAGAUAAGGUCCUUACGUGAGAACAUCUCAGUAUAAUUUUAUUUAAAUACUGCCAUUGACUGUCUGAUCUGUAAGUAUGUGUAUUCAUUAGCAUCUUACAUAAUGCAUAUUAAUUUUUAUGUCAUUUGAAGGCACUAGUUCAUAGCACUUGGAAUUUUCAUUCCAGUUCACCUCUUCAUAUAAAUAAUUGACCCAGUUUUCAAAACUAUAAGUAAUUAUUUUCUUAGCCAUCAGUAAAGAACGCAUAUGGUUACAUGUGCUUGAAAUGUAACAUAACUGGAAGGAAUUCCAAAUGUUUUCUUAUUUUAAGAACUCUGCGGUCAUUCAGUGUUUAUGUGUUGAAUGACUUAUGAGUAAAAUGAAAAUGAAGUAGGACUAAAUUAAUAUACGUAUCCAGAAAUUCACCAUUUCCUCCCACUUUGAACAUCUUUAUUGUGUUCCUUCUUAAAUAUGUAGGAAAUUAAGGAAAUGUUUGCCAGAGAGACUUAGGUGAGUAGUUUUUCUUUUCUGAGUAUAAGGAGAGCAAACAAUUAAAAGAUAAUUUUACUGUGGUCAGUUUUUGUGACCCUGUACCAUCUUUGUAAUGUCUGCCUUCCAGCUUUAGUGCAUUACAAUAGGGAUCAAAUGUCUAUAUUUUAAGAAUAUCAUUGGUAGCUUUUUGAAAGUUGAUAGAUUUAAGUGUAAACCAGUGUUUGAACAUGAAGCUCUGGAACACACUUUUGUAACAUCACCUUUUAAUAAAGGUAGCUCAACAGUUGGAGACAAUAAUGACUUCUUGUUUAACAUGAUAUGUGAUUUAUACAGACUAAUUUGUGUUUAUAGUAAUUAUUUUACCCUGGUUAACUACCUGUGUUAAAAUUUCUUUGUUUUCUGGCUUCAUACUACCCAGUUGUUUUUUUUCUUACUUGAAUGCAUGUAUCCUUGACUUUUCUAAACAUUUUUAAACACAGGGUUUAUGUAGGACUUGUUCCAAACUAAUAGGUACUUUGUUCUUUUUAAACACGUUGGUUUAUAUUAAUGAAAUUGGCUAAUUUGUUUUUGUAAAGUUUUGUUUUCUUAAAGGGGGGAUGAGUUUUGGGGGACUAAAUCAUACUGAACAUGCACUAUACCUUUAGUGUUUUGGUAAAUUUAUGUUACUUAUUAAUUGCCAUGACUUUUUGACAACAAACGUCAUAUUUGAAAUUCUACUGAAAGAAAGUAUAACAGUGUGAUAUUGUUCAUUUGUGAUGUGAUAAUUGUUCAUUAACAAUAUCUAAAAUCUGUAAUAGAUUAGAAAACAAAAUCCCAGCGUGUUUUUUCCCCAUUGAUAAAGAUAGAUUUAGAAAGACCAUAUUUUAAAUAUGUCAUAGUACUGCUAACCGAAAGUUAAGAGUUUUAGUGUUGUAGGAGUUAUGCUAGUAAGUAAUGUUUAUACAAUUCUGAUAAACAUUUCCCCAUGACUGAAUUUUGAGUGGAAAACUUUGUUUCUUAAAAGGCUCUAAGUGGAAGAAAAAAAUAUUAGAGUCUGUCUUCUUAUCGUGUAGUGUGUGUGUGUGUGUGUGUGUGUGUGUGUGUGUGUGUGUUUAGAUCCAGCUUAAUACCAAGUAAUGCCAACAUCUGGCAGAGAGAUGGAGAUCUGGGAAUUUGUUGCUUGAAACCCUGGGACAAAGUGUUCUGAUCUGACCGGCGAACAUAGCUGUAGACUUGAACUGAAAUCUUCAGGGGCAGAAACGUCUUAAGUGUCUGGAAAAUUGGCCUGUUGAGUCACCGUGAAGGCACUAAAACAAAACUAAUUUUAAGCAGGUCAAAGUUCAGUGAUUCCCUCUGGAAUUCAAACUUUUUUUUAAGAGUCUCAUGUUUAAGUGAAAAGGGUCAAAGUUGAUGCACUGUUACAAUGUUUUGAAUGCUUUCCCUUAAGAACAGCCACCCAAGCUGGGAUUAGCAUGAGGAACUGCAAGGCUGGCACUUCAGCGUCUGGGUUAAAAAUAUUUUAAAGCAGUAAAUGCAGUCAGUACAGAGAGAUCCCUGGGAGCCUUUCUAUUCAAAAAUGUGUGAGCUCAGGGCAGCGACUGCAAUGUAAUUUAGGGCAGUGUAUGCUUCAUAGCUUUGGAGAAUAUUGCUUCCCGUUAAUGUUCCAUCGGAGGAUGGUAGGAUAGUAGUAAUUUUAGAAGGUGGUAUUCCUGUUUGUCUUACAUCGAAAACUUCAGAAUAAAUAAAAGGAAACAUCAAUCGAACAAGAAAUGUAACUGUGGAAAAGUACCAAUGAAUCUAAAUUUGAACUGAACAGAUACAAAACCAGCAUGGGUGUAGGAAUAUUUUUAAAGAGGAAGCUAUGGCAAAAGCAACUUCCCAGGGGAUGGACUGAGCAGGCUUUUUAAACGGUCCAAGGUGUAGAGCCAUACUUCAGGAGGAUCCUCAGAAGUUUUGGACAAGCCUCCCCAAAUGUGGCAGGUGCUGUGCUGGCCAUUGGUGACCCAAAGAUGAUGAAAAAUAUGUUCCUGCCCACAAGGAGUUAGCGACCUACUGGGCUUUCCUCUUGCUGAUGACAUGAUUCCUGUUUGAAUCUGUUGACAAGAUUCUGAAAGCUGAACAGAGAAUUCUGGCACUGCACUGGGUAGGAAAAAGCAUUUCAAGAAAUAGAUAAUAUCAAGGACAUCAGGACACCGGGAGUGGGAGAGAUUGGACUGGGAGACUCAGCAGGAUGUCUUCCAAGCGACCAGCCUCUCCGUAUGGGGAAGCAGAUGGAGAGGUAGCCAUGGUGACAAGCAGACAGAAAGUGGAAGAAGAGGAGAGUGACGGGCUCCCAGCCUUUCACCUUCCCUUGCAUGUGAGUUUUCCCAACAAGCCUCACUCUGAGGAAUUUCAGCCAGUUUCUCUGCUGACGCAAGAGACUUGUGGCCAUAGGACUCCCACUUCUCAGCACAAUACAAUGGAAGUUGAUGGCAAUAAAGUUAUGUCUUCAUUUGCCCCACACAACUCAUCUACCUCACCUCAGAAGGCAGAAGAAGGUGGGCGACAGAGUGGCGAGUCCUUGUCUAGUACAGCCCUGGGAACUCCUGAACGGCGCAAGGGCAGUUUAGCUGAUGUUGUUGACACCUUGAAGCAGAGGAAAAUGGAAGAGCUCAUCAAAAACGAGCCGGAAGAAACCCCCAGUAUUGAAAAACUACUCUCAAAGGACUGGAAAGACAAGCUUCUUGCAAUGGGAUCGGGGAACUUUGGCGAAAUAAAAGGGACUCCCGAGAGCUUAGCUGAGAAAGAAAGGCAACUCAUGGGUAUGAUCAACCAGCUGACCAGCCUCCGAGAGCAGCUGUUGGCUGCCCACGAUGAGCAGAAGAAACUAGCUGCCUCUCAGAUUGAGAAACAGCGUCAGCAAAUGGAGCUGGCCAAGCAGCAACAAGAACAAAUUGCAAGACAGCAGCAGCAGCUUCUACAGCAACAACACAAAAUCAAUUUGCUCCAGCAACAGAUCCAGCAGGUUCAAGGUCAGCUGCCGCCAUUAAUGAUUCCCGUAUUCCCUCCUGAUCAACGGACACUGGCUGCAGCUGCCCAGCAAGGAUUCCUCCUCCCUCCAGGCUUCAGCUAUAAGGCUGGAUGUAGUGACCCUUACCCUGUUCAGCUGAUCCCAACUACCAUGGCAGCUGCUGCCGCAGCAACACCAGGCUUAGGCCCACUCCAACUGCAGCAGUUAUAUGCUGCCCAGCUAGCUGCAAUGCAGGUAUCUCCAGGAGGGAAGCUGCCAGGCAUACCCCAAGGCAACCUUGGUGCUGCUGUAUCUCCUACCAGCAUUCACACAGACAAGAGCACAAACAGCCCACCACCCAAAAGCAAGGAUGAAGUGGCACAGCCACUGAACCUAUCAGCUAAACCCAAGACCUCUGAUGGCAAAUCACCCACAUCACCCACCUCUCCCCAUAUGCCAGCUCUGAGAAUAAACAGUGGGGCAGGCCCCCUCAAAGCCUCUGUCCCAGCAGCGUUAGCUAGUCCUUCAGCCAGAGUUAGCACAAUAGGUUACUUAAAUGACCAUGAUGCUGUCACCAAGGCAAUCCAAGAAGCUCGGCAAAUGAAGGAGCAACUCCGACGGGAACAACAGGUGCUUGAUGGGAAGGUGGCUGUUGUGAAUAGUCUGGGUCUCAAUAACUGCCGAACAGAAAAGGAAAAAACAACACUGGAGAGUCUGACUCAGCAACUGGCAGUUAAACAGAAUGAAGAAGGAAAAUUUAGCCAUGCAAUGAUGGAUUUCAAUCUGAGUGGAGAUUCUGAUGGAAGUGCUGGAGUCUCAGAGUCAAGAAUUUAUAGGGAAUCCCGAGGGCGUGGUAGCAAUGAACCCCACAUAAAGCGUCCAAUGAAUGCCUUCAUGGUGUGGGCUAAAGAUGAACGGAGAAAGAUCCUUCAAGCCUUUCCUGACAUGCACAACUCCAACAUCAGCAAGAUAUUGGGAUCUCGCUGGAAAGCUAUGACAAACCUAGAGAAACAGCCAUAUUAUGAGGAGCAAGCCCGUCUCAGCAAGCAGCACCUGGAGAAGUACCCUGACUAUAAGUACAAGCCCAGGCCAAAGCGCACCUGCCUGGUGGAUGGCAAAAAGCUGCGCAUUGGUGAAUACAAGGCAAUCAUGCGCAACAGGCGGCAGGAAAUGCGGCAGUACUUCAAUGUUGGGCAACAAGCACAGAUCCCCAUUGCCACUGCUGGUGUUGUGUACCCUGGAGCCAUCGCCAUGGCUGGGAUGCCCUCCCCUCACCUGCCCUCGGAGCACUCAAGCGUGUCUAGCAGCCCAGAGCCUGGGAUGCCUGUUAUCCAGAGCACUUACGGUGUGAAAGGAGAGGAGCCACAUAUCAAAGAAGAGAUACAGGCCGAGGACAUCAAUGGAGAAAUUUAUGAUGAGUACGACGAGGAAGAGGAUGAUCCAGAUGUAGAUUAUGGGAGUGACAGUGAAAACCAUAUUGCAGGACAAGCCAACUGAUAAGGGUCAAAAGAUUGUUGUGACCUUAGGACUUAAAGAAGCCCUAACUGGUUCAUCCUUACCAGUGGCCAAGCACAUUAACUUUCUCAUACACUGACUGUUACUUUAACUGUUAGUCUUAAAUAGUUGGGACAUCAGCUGACUAAUAGACCUCAGCCUCAAAAGGCUUGGAAAGAAAAAACAAAUACAACAAGCAAACAACAAUAUCAACAACAAGAGAUUGAAAUAAGCUAUGGGUAAAAUAAUGCCAGUAAUUCAGCUGCUACAUCCAAGCACUGAAGUCUUACCCGUCAACUUUUUUUUUUUUUUAAAUAAACUUUAUGGCUGUUUGUUCUACAAUGUUCUAGAAAUUCUCACUCAGGUACACAGUGCCAACAAGUGGCUUGUGAAUGUGUUUUGUUGUUUUGUGCUACAAUUUUUAAAAAGAAAAAAGUUUUGUUUUGUUUUUUGGGGUUUCUGGGUUUUUUCCUUUUCUUUUUCUUUCCUUUCAUUUUUUUUCUUUGUAAUGCACCUGACAGAAAAAAAAGAAAAAUGAAUUUCUCUUUACUUCUCUCCACCUUCUCCAUCUCUCUACUUUAAAGAUGGAAGUCUGUGCAUGAGGGGAAAGAGGGAAAAAGAGCCUGUUUUUAACUUCCUUGCUAUCCACCACAAAAUAAGCAAUUAUUUUCUUUAGAGGACUUUAUCUAUUGCACACCACACUACAUCUUUGAGCAAGUGCCAAAUUUGUACUGAAGUGUUGACCAAGUUCAUUUUUUCUCUUUACUUUUUCCUUUUCCUUCUUAAGUUAGGACAGUGUUAAAUCUUAGACAAUCCCUUGAAAAACCUGAAAUACCAGCAGCUGGUGAGAUUUGACUUUUUUUUUUAAUGGAAACUGUAGGUGCUGUUCUCAGGUGAAAAGAGAGAGAGAGAGAGAGACAUAAGAAAUUUAGAGAAAAAUAUUUUCUGAUCUUGGAUUUUUGUGUGUAUGUAUGUAUGUGAUUAUGGUACUAAUAAUAGGAAUAACGUUGGACCAUUGUGAGUUAAACCCACAUCUGGGGAUGAAAUCCCACAUCCUCCCAAGUGACUGGUCUAGAAAUAAUCUUGACCUUGACUUUGCACUUCAAAUGACAACUUAACCAAGUAUAGGGCUCAGAAAUUAUAUUUUUAAAUGUCUGAUUAUUAUUGGAUGGAUCAGGUGGCCCUGUGUAAUAGAGGUGUGCAUGUAUAACAUGGAAGCUACUAGCAAACUGCUCCCAGAUGUCCUUUCUCCCUGGUCAGUUGGUUCCAUUAACGUUUGCUACUUAGUGAUUUUUGUUUUUCCUGUUGAUAUUUUGAGCAAAACAAUCAUUGUUUUCAUUGAAUAUAUUUGGCCAUUUUUUCAGACAAAUAGAAUUAGCUUAUUUCUUCAACAUUCCAUCCUUUCCCGAUCAGGAAAUGAAACUGAUGAUUUUAUAAGGUAUUUUUCACCCCUCCAUGAAGUGAGGUGGAGGCCUUUAGCAUUUCAGAAGUGUGGGCCAUAUGUAGUUCAUGCCAUAAAAAGUAGGAUUUAAUUAAAAGUCAUUGCAGCCCAAUAAAAUGGAGCCUGGCUGCACCCAGGGAUCCUUGCCACUGCUCUUCCCUUGCUGUCAGAUUAAUCCACUGAAGUCCAACUUUGGUUCAAGCAGAGUAUUUGCAAAGAGCAACAACUGAAUGUGAUGGGACUGCUUAUGUAGAUUUUGCCAGCCAAAUGCCAAGGCAGUUGUAGGGCCUGUACAAAUAAAUGCAAAAUCAUUUCAAGUCAAUUGCCAUUAUUUGUAUUGAAGUAUCAGAUAGAUAGUAAAUACUGCAACUAGUAGCUUGAUGUGCUAUAGUUUUCACUCCAGUCAUCAUUUUCCUAUCUCACCCCCCGAAACACCACCCUAAAGUUGGAUUUUUACAUAUAAAUAAAAAAAGAAUCCCUUUUAUUUUUCUCUCUCUCAGAAGACUUGCUCUGGGGUUUUGCUUGGAGGAGCUGAUCAUAUCCUGCAUGUCAGAGAUUUCAUUUUGUUUGUUUUUCUGUUUGUUUGUUUUUGAUGACUUUAUUUACAUUUGAACUGCCUCUUUUUGCUAGUGUUGUAAUGAUGAUGAUGAUAAAAUAAUAAUAAUAAUAGUAAUAAUAAUAAUAAUGGUCAGCUGUUCCCAGAUUAGUAAGUUAUGUAUAAUUUAUUUUAUUUCUCCCUUUCUAUUUUAUUCUGCUCUGAUUUGGAAGUGCAGCCAAUAAGCUGUUAGAUAUUUAAAACAAAUUUCCAUCUCCAACUCAUAUAUGUAUGUAUAUGUAUAUAUAUAUAUACAUAUAUAUACACACAUAUACACACACACACACACAUUUACCCACAAUUUUACUUCUCUUUCCGUAAGUUUUCUCUUUUUUAAGAAUUUUGGCCCCAACAAUAUCAGUUCUGAUGUUUAAAACAAAGGAGUGAAUUAAUAGGAGGGUCGUGUUCAAUCUUAAUUAACUUAUGCUCUCAUCACUCAUUUUAGUUAUUUAAUUGCCACAGUCAUCUAGAGCCAAUUUUUUUUUGUUUUUGUUUGUUUUGUUUUUAAGCACUCUGGAUAAGGAAAAAAUAGACACUUGUUUUUAUAUCAUUUUUAUGUACAAUGUGAAAACAGAUUUUUAAAAAAUUUGUUCUCUGUCUUUGUUAACAAAUUCCUUCCGAUUUAUGUGGGUUCACCUCUCACGUUUGCUGGAUACUUACUUUACACCAUGUUAUGAAAGAUGCUUUGUUUUCAUUUCAUGAGUUUGGGCUACAAGAAUACUUUGUUUUAGCUCCAGGUAGAUGCCAUUGAAGGCAUUCAUGGCUGAAAUCAAUUCUAACACACUUACCGAUGAAUUGACAACACUUUGGUGUUUGGUCUUUUUUUUGUUAUAUUUUGUUUUAUUUGAAGGGGAAAACAAAAUUGUUAAUGGUGACUUUUAACUGCUGAAAUUCAAAAUUUGAUUUUAGUUAGGUUUAUGUCCGAGACUAAACUGUGCAUGAACCGAAACAAAAAGCAAGUUCAUACCGCUGCAUUCUGUUCUCUUGUUCUGACGGUUAAUUCACUGGACAUCAAAUUUUCUUUGCCCUAGUUUUCCCCAAAAGAAAACAAAAGCAAAAAUAGUUAUAUUAAUGUUGAAAGUGCUUUGAAGUCACUUGAUAAAAGGUGCUAUGAAUAGCAACUUACUGUGUUACUACAUUGCCUUUUUGGCAUUGGUUGAUUUAUAAUUUUGGUAAAGGAUCCUAAAACCCUGUAUUCUUUUUCUGUGCCCCAUAAUGACCAAAAAAGAUAAAGAAAAUGAGAGUAAGAUCAAAAGAUCAAACUAAAACAUAAACAGUCUCCUUCCUGUCUGCUUUCUUACCUAUCUGUUCACACUUUAUCUCUUUCCCUUUCUCUCUCUCUCUCACAUGCGCGCGCGCGCGCGCGCACACACACACACACACACACUUGCCCCAACACUGAGAAAUAAUCUUGCCAGAAUUCUGGUUUUUAUAGUUGUUGUAGUCCGUUUCUCUAAAAAUAGUCCUGUUUUCAUAUGAAUCUAAGAGAACAUUACCGGAGAAAAUAAAGUUACUCAUUUAUAGUUACUAAUAAUAAGUUAGUGAUUAACUUACCACAAUUGGAUAAAAUAUAAAACUAUUCUUCAGCACAUUUAUACCUAAAUUAGUGAAGUCCAUUUGUGAAGUUCAUUUGGCAUCUGCAGUUAAGAGUUAACCAUGUAUAAAAUCCCUCCCAAAGAACAUAAUCAUCGUUAGAACCAAAUCCUCUUAUAAAGAACAAAUAUAAAAAAGUUUUCUGUGGUGAAGCUAUUUUAUAGAUUUGAUUUCCGGAGUAGAAUUUUACCUUAAUUCACUUAAAGAAAAUUAACCAUUUUUUGGUCCAACUUCAGAUAUUUUCUUAAUCCAGAAGCUGUGACUGUUCCCAGAAGAAACCUCUUAUAUCACAUUUAAAACAUAAAAAAUAAUUACACUUUCACUCAUUCUAAUGGGUAAAUUGUUGAAUUGUAAUAAACAACUGUAUAUUUACAAACAGGUUUAUAAGGUAUUUGUCUAUCAAAUUAAUAAUAAAAUAAAACUUACGGGGUCUGCAAGGAAAACUAUGAAGGCCACUUAAAGUGGUUCAGGUAUCCCUUUGUCUUGUAGGGCAUAGCUGUUGGUUUAGCCAGGCUUUUACAGUAUUUAAUUUUAAAGUAUCCUAUAACUAUCAACUUCCCAGGUUGAAGACGAUGUGUUGAGUUUCCUACUGAUUGAUUGAUUCCUGUCCUCCCCAGUGUUUCCGUCACUGGUUCACUAAAACAGUAUUUAUAUAGCUCCACUGGCUCUAAAGCUCUUAGUCCUUCUAAUAUUUUGGAUUUUACAAGUAAAAAUGGAAAAAAAAUAGAAAAGAGACAAUCAAAUGCCUGGAGCUUAAAACAAAGUAUGUGCAACCUACCAUCUCACUUGAAAUUUAAUAAAAUAAUAAGUAAUUAUGUAAAUAUAACAUAGAGUUAUAGAUUUAUAUUUUGUUCAUAACACAUAGUGUAAUAUAAGUUGUAUAUUUUCAUGUUUUUGGUUUUAUGUUAUCAUUCAUGCCACAAUAAAAAUAAAACAGGAGUUUAUGUGCUCUUAAAAAAAAGAUGUGGGUUGCCACCAACCUGUUUUUCGUUUUUGUUUUUUGUUUAUUUUAUUUUAUUUUUUUGCAUUCUCCUUUUUCAGUAUUACUGCCAUGCAAGGCACCAAUAAAAACAGCAAAUGUGUUCUUUA